GGAGAGGCGGUCGGGAUCCGCUGCGCGAGCUGUCUCGGUCCCACGUGUGCGAGUUGCUACGAUGGAAGUUAAAGGGAAAAAGCAAUUCACAGGAAAGAGUACAAAGACAGCACAAGAAAAAAACAGAUUUCAUAAAAAUAGUGAUUCUGGUUCUUCAAAGACAUUUCCAACAAGGAAAGUUGCUAAAGAAGGUGGACCUAAAGUCACAUCUAGGAACUUUGAGAAAAGUAUCACAAAACUUGGGAAAAAGGGUGUAAAGCAGUUCAAGAAUAAGCAGCAAGGGGACAAAUCACCAAAGAACAAAUUCCAGCCGGCAAAUAAAUUCAACAAGAAGAGAAAAUUCCAGCCAGAUGGUAGAAGCGAUGAAUCAGCAGCCAAGAAGCCCAAAUGGGAUGACUUCAAAAAGAAGAAGAAAGAACUGAAGCAAAGCAGACAACUCAGUGAUAAAACCAACUAUGACAUUGUUGUUCGGGCAAAGCAGAUGUGGGAGAUUUUAAGAAGAAAAGACUGUGACAAAGAAAAAAGAGUAAAGUUAAUGAGUGAUUUGCAGAAGUUGAUUCAAGGGAAAAUUAAAACUAUUGCAUUUGCACACGAUUCAACUCGUGUGAUCCAGUGUUACAUUCAGUAUGGUAAUGAAGAACAGAGAAAACAGGCUUUUGAAGAAUUGCGAGAUGAUUUGGUUGAGUUAAGUAAAGCCAAAUAUUCGAGAAAUAUUGUUAAGAAAUUUCUCAUGUAUGGAAGUAAACCACAGAUUGCAGAGAUAAUCAGAAGUUUUAAAGGCCACGUGAGGAAGAUGCUGCGGCAUGCGGAAGCAUCAGCCAUCGUGGAGUACGCAUACAAUGACAAAGCCAUUUUGGAGCAGAGGAACAUGCUGACGGAAGAGCUCUAUGGGAACACAUUUCAGCUUUACAAGUCAGCAGAUCACCGAACUCUGGACAAAGUGUUAGAGGUACAGCCAGAAAAAUUAGAACUUAUUAUGGAUGAAAUGAAACAGAUUCUAACUCCAAUGGCCCAAAAGGAAGCUGUGAUUAAGCACUCAUUGGUGCAUAAAGUAUUCUUGGACUUUUUUACCUAUGCACCCCCCAAACUCAGAUCAGAAAUGAUUGAAGCCAUCCGCGAAGCGGUGGUCUACCUGGCACACACACACGAUGGCGCCAGAGUGGCCAUGCACUGCCUGUGGCAUGGCACGCCCAAGGACAGGAAAGUGAUUGUGAAAACAAUGAAGACUUAUGUUGAAAAGGUGGCUAAUGGCCAAUACUCCCAUUUGGUUUUACUGGCGGCAUUUGAUUGUAUUGAUGAUACUAAGCUUGUGAAGCAGAUAAUCAUAUCAGAAAUUAUCAGUUCAUUGCCUAGCAUAGUAAAUGACAAAUAUGGAAGGAAGGUCCUAUUGUACUUACUAAGCCCCAGAGAUCCUGCACAUACAGUACGAGAAAUCAUUGAAGUUCUGCAAAAAGGAGAUGGAAAUGCACACAGUAAGAAAGAUACAGAGGUCCGCAGACGGGAGCUCCUAGAAUCCAUUUCUCCAGCUUUGUUAAGCUACCUGCAAGAACACGCCCAAGAAGUGGUGCUAGAUAAGUCUGCGUGUGUGUUGGUGUCUGACAUUCUGGGAUCUGCCACUGGAGACGUUCAGCCUACCAUGAAUGCCAUCGCCAGCUUGGCAGCAACAGGACUGCAUCCUGGUGGCAAGGACGGAGAGCUUCACAUUGCAGAACAUCCUGCAGGACAUCUAGUUCUGAAGUGGUUAAUAGAGCAAGAUAAAAAGAUGAAAGAAAAUGGGAGAGAAGGUUGUUUUGCAAAAACACUUGUAGAGCAUGUUGGUAUGAAGAACCUGAAGUCCUGGGCUAGUGUAAAUCGAGGUGCCAUUAUUCUUUCUAGCCUCCUCCAGAGUUGUGACCUGGAAGUUGCAAACAAAGUCAAAGCUGCACUGAAAAGCUUGAUUCCUACAUUGGAAAAAACCAAAAGCACCAGCAAAGGAAUAGAAAUUCUACUUGAAAAACUGAGCACAUAGGUGGAAAGAGUUAAGAGCAAGAUGGAAUGAUUUUUUCUGUUCUCUGUUCUGUUUCCCAAUGCAGAAAAGAAGGGGUAGGGUCCACCAUACUGGUAAUUGGGGUACUCUGUAUAUGUGUUUCUUCUUUGUAUACGAAUCUAUUUAUAUAAAUUGUUUUUUUAAAUGGUCUUUUUUAAAAA